AUUUCCCCUGUGUACUCCUGGCUCGGCUGGCCGGCUAAGGCAGUUUCUCAUCACUGAUGUGCUCUGGGACAGCUGAGUGGGAUGGGCUCCUCUGGGGUGGGUGUGGAGGAGUGGUCGUGAUGCCUGGAACACUGCAGUCACUCCUCAGAGACACGACUUGGCAGCCCUCCUGAGCCUGCCUGGUCACAUGCUGCCUGUCUUGGAAGGUCCUCUGUCCCAAGCAGUGGAUGUGCAGUUUCUUCACCCCUGCUUAGCUUCAUCAGGCACAAUGCGUCUUUGAGGUUGCCCUUUUCAUGGUUUGCUCAUAUUCUACCCAGAAAAGACUUAGGAGACUUAGAAGAAGUUAGUACUUUGCAUCCUACCUACACUGCUCUCCUUGGAGGAAGACCUUAUUCUGGAUUUUACAGAGCAAAUCAGAUCUGAUGUUUGUAGCUUCCAAUGUGCUAUGGAGCUUCCUCCUGCAGAGUGACUUGGGUCUGGAGAGCCUGAUAUUUGCAACUGAUGUCUGCAGCUUCCAGUGUACCUGCUAGCCCUUAUAAACCUCACACCAGUACUUUGAGGUCAGAGUUAUUCAAGAGCUUACUGAGACAACAGGCCCUGAGAAGCUAAGCGAUUUGCCCUGUGGCAUGGAUGGUAGAGAGGGGAGCUGGCACUUGAACUCAGGUCUGGCUCGACCUCAGAAUGAGUGAUCUUGUGUCUCUGUGCCCCAGGACUGCAUCCUCUCACCAAUACUUCACCAGCCUAGGGAUCUGUGCUCCCAAGAGCCUGUUGACAUUGUAAACCUGAAUCCAAUCCAUAAACCAAAAGCCCAGGCUUAGAAUCACAUUGUGGUGGAGCGGGUGUUUGGUGGAGUCCCUGAUUCAAAAUGUUUGACAAGGAAGCCUGACCAUUUGUCUUCUGUUGGGUGUUUGGAGUCCAAGAGACCUGAGAUCAGAGUCCAGCAUUGUCACUUCAUCCAGCCUUGGCAGUGUGGGAUGUGACUCUGCCUCUGAACCGCAGUUAUACCAUCUGUGCUGGUGGCGUUGUGAGGAUGGCAGGUAACAAAGGUGAAGCUCCUGGCCCCAGUGGGCCUUCAAGGAUGGCAGCUGCUCCUGCCCCCUACUGGGGUUGCACUCAUUCGUUGCCUGCUCUGGGGAGUCCUAUGGGGUUUCUUAGCUGGCCCUGCCCAUGGUGGAGAAAGAGGGAUCCACCCAUUGCUGAUUGGGCCCAGAGGAAAUGAGGACACUGCGUGAAGCCAAGACAGCAGACGCCCUGCUGGCGGACUUGGAGUCUACCACCUCCCACAUCUCCAAACGGCCUGUGUUCUUGUCGGAGGAGACCCCCUACUCAUACCCAACUGGAAACCACACAUACCAGGAGAUUGCCGUGCCACCCCCCGUCCCCCCACCCCCGUCCAGCGAGGCCCUCAAUGGCACAAUCCUUGACCCCUUAGACCAGUGGCAGCCCAGCAGCUCCCGAUUCAUCCACCAGCAGCCUCAGUCCUCAUCACCUGUGUACGGCUCCAGUGCCAAAACUUCCAGUGUCUCCAACCCUCAGGACAGUGUUGGCUCUCCGUGCUCCCGAGUGGGUGAGGAGGAGCACGUCUACAGCUUCCCCAACAAGCAGAAAUCAGCUGAGCCUUCACCCACCGUAAUGAGCACGUCCCUGGGCAGCAACCUUUCUGAACUCGACCGCCUGCUGCUGGAACUGAACGCUGUACAGCAUAACCCGCCAGGCUUCCCUGCAGAUGAGGCCAACUCAAGCCCCCCGCUUCCUGGGGCCCUGAGCCCCCUCUAUGGUGUCCCAGAGACUAACAGCCCCUUGGGAGGCAAAGCUGGGCCCCUGACGAAAGAGAAGCCUAAGCGGAAUGGGGGCCGGGGCCUGGAGGACGUGCGGCCCAGUGUGGAGAGUCUCUUGGAUGAACUGGAGAGCUCCGUGCCCAGCCCCGUCCCUGCCAUCACUGUGAACCAGGGCGAGAUGAGCAGCCCGCAGCGCGUCACCUCCACCCAACAGCAGACACGCAUCUCGGCCUCCUCUGCCACCAGGGAGCUGGACGAGCUGAUGGCUUCGCUGUCGGAUUUCAAGACCAGCUCCUCCACUGUGGCUCUGAGUGCCCCGGGGCUGUCCAGCUCUGCUCCGUCCUCAUACUGCUCCCUUCCUCCUUCUCCUCCUCCCAUGCCAUCUGUAUUUCUGCCACCCACCACUAUACCCUCCCCUCGAGGCCAGGGCCACACUCCGGAGUUCCCUUGUACUGAGCAGAGUGGACGAGGCCUUCUACCUCCUGUAGCCCCCAGCUGGCUUGAUUUGGCUGGUCUUGGGGUGAUGCCUGACACCUUCAACUCAAGGUCUCCCUCUGUGGAGGGUUCUCUGUGGGCAGUGGGCACAGAGAGUCAGGGUCGAGAUUGGAGGCACCUGCCGACCAUCACAAGUGAGCUCUCUGGGGCUCCCCGCUGCCACACUGUACCCUGUGCUGGGAGCACAGCUCUCCAAGAGCCUGGGGAGCCCCAGGGGCCACCAGCCAGCCCUUCGUGCCCAGAGGAGGCCUUGGCUGCCACAUGGGAGCAGCCAUGGGCUUCGGAGGUAUUCGGGCCUGAGAGAAUGCCCCCCUCUGGAGCUGCUCGAAGCUUCCAAGAAGUAACAGAGCCAGCUGUAGUGGCAGUGGACCGGCAGGCCAUCUUCCCAGAUACCUGGACUCUCACGGAGGAACAUGGCCUACAGCAGGAGAGGCCAAGGCCAGAGCCAGGGAGGCUGGGAAGCAGCUCCCCUGCCUCAGUUACCACGGAGCAGCUAGGUGCAAAGAUGACCGAGAGGGGAAGUGUGGCCAGGCCAACCCAGGGACCUGAAACCCCAAGGAGCCCAGAGGGCACCACGGAAGCUGCCACCCAGGACGGGAAGGAACAGCCAGAGCUUCCAUGUGCCAUGGCCAUGGGCACACCCAGCACCACGGAGAGGAUUUCCACCUCUGGCCAGAUCCGAUCUGUGAUCAGGAGGAGCUGGGAGUCUGGCCACGCACACCCCAUGUCCCGGGAGCCCUCCCCUCGCCGCCGGCUGGACCCUGCCACCUUGAGCAGGACCCCAUCCCAGGAACAGCUCAUCGCGGAGCUGCAGGGGCGGCUGGGCAUCCAGCCUGAGGCAGAGGAGCCGGCGGAGGCGGCGGGGCCCUCUGCCCAGGACUGGCUGACCGAGGGCGUCAUCAUCACUGUGCAGCCACGUGGGAAGCGGGCCGGGGGGCAGCUCGUAGAGAAGGUUGUCUUCCCUCCUGGCUCUCCCAUUCCCCUGAGAAGAACCAUCUCUGUCCUGGCUUCUCCUUCUGUCCCUUUGCUCCAGCAUCGCACAGACGCCGCGGCCAGCAGCUCUUCUCCCCUGCCCAGCCUGCUCGCCUCCUCCCCCCUGGGGCCCUCAGCUUAUACCUGUGGUUCUUCUGGGGUCCAGAGUGCAGGGGAAGAGCCCCAUGAUGAGGGGGUGCAGGGCCCUGCCCUUCCCAUUCCUGCACCCCACACCAUGAGGUCCGUGGGCUGCCAGACUGAUGAGGACCCGCUCUUCCCCCCGAUGCAGAUCCAGGGCCUGGAGCAAAGAGCGGAUGGGGAGCGGUGCUGGGCGGCCGGCUGGCCUCGGGACGGCGGGCGGAGCAGCCCCGGAGGGCAGGACGAGGGAGGGGGCUCCUGGCCCCUGGAGGAGGUUGUACUUCUUGUCUCCAUCAGCUCAUCUGUCCAGGAGGGAGAAAAGUACCCCCAUCCCUGUGCUGCCAGACACCGUACCCCGAGCCUCAGGAGUCCUGACCAGCCCCCUCCGUGUCCACAGUUCAUGGCCCAGGGGAAGACAGGGAGCAGCUCACCCCCUGGGGGGCCCCCGAAGCCCGGGAGCCAGCUGGACAGCAUGCUGGGGAGCCUGCAGUCUGACCUGAACAAGCUGGGGGUCGCCACAGUCGCCAAAGGAGUCUGCGGGGCCUGCAAGAAGCCCAUCGCCGGGCAGGUUGUGACCGCCAUGGGGAAGACGUGGCACCCCGAGCACUUCGUCUGCACCCACUGCCAGGAGGAGAUCGGAUCCCGGAACUUCUUCGAGCGGGAUGGACAGCCCUACUGUGAAAAGGACUACCACAACCUCUUCUCCCCGCGCUGCUACUACUGCAACGGCCCCAUCCUGGAUAAAGUGGUGACAGCCCUUGACCGGACGUGGCACCCUGAACACUUCUUCUGUGCACAGUGUGGAGCCUUCUUUGGUCCCGAAGGGUUCCACGAGAAGGACGGCAAGGCCUACUGUCGCAAGGACUACUUCGACAUGUUCGCACCCAAGUGUGGCGGCUGCGCCCGGGCCAUCCUGGAGAACUAUAUCUCAGCCCUCAACACGCUGUGGCAUCCUGAGUGCUUUGUGUGCCGGGAAUGCUUCACGCCAUUCGUGAACGGCAGCUUCUUCGAGCACGACGGGCAGCCCUACUGUGAGGUGCACUACCACGAGCGGCGCGGCUCGCUGUGUUCUGGCUGCCAGAAGCCCAUCACCGGCCGCUGCAUCACCGCCAUGGCCAAGAAGUUCCACCCCGAGCACUUCGUCUGUGCCUUCUGCCUCAAGCAGCUCAACAAGGGCACCUUCAAGGAGCAGAACGACAAGCCUUACUGUCAGAACUGCUUCCUCAAGCUCUUCUGCUAGGUGCCCUGCCCCUGUCUCUGCCCCCCUUCCCCAGCCAGCAUCCCCAACUGCGACUGUGACCUAGAGACUUCACCCGGGGGUGAAGGGGUAAACCCGACUGAAACUGGAACCCUUGUCCUCCGCUGGUGCGGGAUGGACAGAGGGCCGUGAGGGGUCCCCCUGCUUGUCUUCACCCCUGCCAGAGCCUCUGGGCCCCCUCCUCCCUCCUGUAGCUCUCCCUAGGCUGCCCACUCUCCAUCCUCCCCAGGGGUAGAGGCUGGGGGCUCCACCCCAGCCCAUGUACGUCCCCACGAACUGGCCUGGCCAGCACCCCACACUGGAGCCAUCUCUUCCUCAUAUUUCAGCAGUGCAGCCGGGGGGCAGGGAAGGGCAGGCAGGGUCUGUUGGGGUCUCUUUUUAUCCUUAUUCCUCCCCCGACCUAAUUGUCUUUGUUCUGUGAUUAUUGGGGGACACCCGGCUCCCUCCAGACAAUGCCAGCAUAAAUCCAUCCAUCCAAAGGCAGAGAACCAAAGGGGCCAUGGAAGGUUCUCUGUGCUCCUCCUACCCUUCCAGUGCCCUAGGCCUGGCGACUGCCCCUGCCUUUUAGACCCGCCCUCCCCUUUUAUACCUGCUCUUGUUCUACUGAGAAAAGCCUCUCCAGCAAUAAUGUUUUCUAGUCACUUCCUCCGUCUCCGGGACGGCGUGCCUGGACACUGUACCGACUUUGAUAGAUUUCUACACUGAGGUUUGAAUUCAUAUCGCCUGAGUUGCUUUUACUUCUCUAUACAAAAUGAUUUUGAAGAGAUUUUAAAGACGUUCCCUUUUGUAUUCUCUUCCUCAUCCACCGCCACUGGGCCUGUCACUGAUGGUGGCUCUGGUGUGAAGUUUGCUUUGUACUGAGGGUUGGGGUGGGGAAGCAAUUUGUAUUUUAUUGUUUCUUAGCACAAGCAGGUGAACUGGGAGCAGCUCUGUGACUCCCCCUCUUUCACUUCAUAGCUCACCAGGACUGUUUUAUAAACUGCUGUAUUUGGAAACCCCUUCUUUACUUCCCAGGCCAGCAAGCUCUUCACUGAAACUGGUUGAAGGGUGUUGCACCCUUUUGGGCCUAGAAUUCUGAACUUUAUCUGUUCUGUUUCUGUGGGAGGAGAAGGGGAAGUAUGUUUUGGGGGGCUGCUUCCUGUCUGAGUAAGCCCUCAGGAGCCUCUGCUCCCCUGUGAACCCACUGAACCUUCUGAGCCCCCACUGCUUCUAUGGGGCUCUCUCUUCUGCCUUCUCAGGAAAGCUGGUGUCUGAUUUUGGCCAUCAGGACUCUGACGUCUCUUUGGUCUUGUUGAUUUCCUCUGGGCAUAUCCCUUCCCCAGAUCUGCUCCUCCCCUUUCACAGGUGGGAUCGGCACUCAGGGGGUCUGGAAAGAAGGUCAUAAGGGAGCAUGAUAGGAUUUGGGGCAGAGGGACAGGCUCCUCUGGGGAAACCCCCCAGAGCUCUUUACCAAGGAUGAAAGAGGAGCCAGGCCUUGGGCUCCUGAUGAGGAGAAAGGGGCCCCACCGGGGUCUAAUGGUGACAGUCCAAACCACUCCACUGGCCUCCUGGCAGAAGCCGAGUGUGCUGGGGUCUCCGAAGAGGGUCCCUCCUUUUUGGGGGAAGGUCAGCCCAGCCCCUCCAAAGGUCUGAUGUCUCCACUUUCACCCGCAGGCCUUACCGCUCUGUUUAUAGUGACCCACCCUAGAUCUUCCCCAAGAGGGACUGGGGUUUCUGGGGUCCAUUCUCUGAGUCAGUGGUUAUUUGAAAAUUUGAUUUUGAUUUUAUUUUUUCUCUGUAAACUUCCAAGCUGGCUUUUCCCAUUUCAAUUCCUGUGAUUUAUGCCAAUAAAGUUUGCCCAUGAUUUUCA